GCAGCCGCCGGCAGCUACUGCAAGGCAAAAGCCGGAGUGGACGUGUCUUUUGAAACUGCUGCUCUUUCACUUCUCAGGCGUCACCGAGAGCUCAGCACCCAGGCUGAACUCUGUACCAUUUGGAAGAAUGGAAGCUGAUGCAUCUGUUGACAUGUUUUCCAAAGUCCUGGAGCAUCAGCUGCUUCAGACUACCAAACUGGUGGAAGAACAUUUGGAUUCUGAAAUUCAAAAACUGGAUCAGAUGGAUGAGGAUGAAUUGGAACGCCUUAAAGAAAAGAGACUCCAGGCACUAAGGAAAGCUCAACAGCAGAAACAAGAAUGGCUUUCUAAAGGACAUGGGGAAUACAGAGAAAUCCCUAGUGAAAGAGACUUUUUUCAAGAAGUCAAGGAGAGUGAAAAUGUGGUUUGCCAUUUCUACAGAGACUCCACAUUCAGGUGUAAAAUACUAGACAGACAUCUGGCAAUAUUGUCCAAGAAACACCUCGAGACCAAAUUUUUGAAGCUGAAUGUGGAAAAAGCACCUUUCCUUUGUGAGAGACUGCAUAUCAAAGUCAUUCCCACACUAGCACUGCUAAAAGAUGGGAAAACACAAGAUUAUGUUGUUGGGUUUACUGACCUAGGAAAUACAGAUGACUUCACCACAGAAACUUUAGAAUGGAGGCUCGGUUCUUCUGACAUUCUUAAUUACAGUGGAAAUUUAAUGGAGCCACCAUUUCAGAACCAAAAGAAAUUUGGAACAAACUUCACAAAGCUGGAAAAGAAAACUAUCCGAGGAAAGAAAUAUGAUUCAGACUCUGAUGAUGAUUAGAGCUCAAUAAUUCUUUGUAAAUUGUCUUUUUUUUUCUGCUUCAGAUUUAAAUGUGUUUUUAAAAUUCUAUUAAUGUCUAUACAUUGGUCACCUAAAUACUCAUAUUCUCGAGUUUUAUACAGUUGUAUCACAUCGAAAAGUGUCUUUACUGUUUUCUGUGUGGCCAUCAUGUUUAAGUUGAGGAAAACUCAGUUCUUAAAUUAUCUGGGAAGGGUCUGGAUUCUCUAUUUUUGAGAUUGACUUUAUCACAAUAUGAUUCUUACAUCUUUAUACCAUUUACAAUUGUGUUUUAGAUCUACAGAGUUAGAAAUUCGAAAACUAUUCCAGGACUAAUUCUUAAUCGGCAUUAUUUAUACAAGAGGUCAAGUAACAUUUACUAGCGCAAUACUGCACUUGUAAAUGAAUUAUAAACGCUCUUCUGGAAUAUAUUUAAAUAACCAUUAAAGAACUGCUUAUUCAUUCUGGACACUGCAUGUUGAUGUUGAAUCAACUGAUGCCAGCAGAAAGCUAUUUUGAUUUGUGAACAUACUGCCUUAUUUAAAGGGUCCUGAUUGCUUGUAUUUUAAGACAUUCAUUAAAAAGAAACCAGGAAACACUUUUGAAAUAACAGCAUAAGGAACUUCACUGUCUCUGCUCAAUAAAAUACCUGUAACUGGAAGUUUAUGUGGAAAUUGUCAUAAAAGCAUACAUCCAACAAAAA